CCCCACUCCAAUGAGGUCACAAUGGCUGGAGCUCUGAGGGGCCCAGGCUCCCUGAGCCAGGAGGAGAGGAGAAAGUCCAAGGAAAGAUGGCUGGCAGUCACCCCUAUUUCAACCAGCCUGACUCCACACACCCAUCGCCGCCCUCCGCUCCACCCAGCCUCCGCUGGUACCAGCGCUGCCAGCCCUCUGAUGCCACCAGUGGCCUGCUGGUGGCCCUGCUGGGUGGGGGCCUGCCUGCUGGCUUCGUGGGCCCCCUUUCUCGUAUGGCUUACCAGGCUUCCAACCUGCCCUCGCUGGAGCUGCUCAUCUGGCGAUGCCUCUUCCACCUCCCUAUUGCCCUGCUACUUAAACUGCGUGGCGACCCCCUUCUGGGAACUCCUGACAUCCGAAGCCGGGCCUUCUUCUGUGCCCUGCUCAACAUCCUCAGCAUUGGAUGUGCCUACAGUGCGGUUCAGGUGGUGCCCGCUGGCAACGCUGCCACUGUUCGCAAAGGUUCUUCCACCGUCUGCUCCGCCGUCCUCACUCUCUGCCUUGAGAGCCAGGGUCUCAGUGGCUACGACUGGUGUGGACUGUUGGGCUGCAUCCUAGGACUAAUCAUCAUUGUGGGACCUGGACUCUGGACACUACAGGAGGGGACCACGGGUGUCUACACCGCCCUGGGCUAUGUGGAGGCUUUCCUGGGAGGCCUGGCGCUGUCCCUGAGGCUUCUGGUCUAUCGUUCUCUGCACUUUCCCCCCUGCCUCCCAACAGUGGCCUUCCUAUCUGGCUUGGUGGGGCUGCUGGGCUCUGUGCCAGGCCUCUUUGUGCUGCAGGCCCCCGUGUUGCCCAGUGACCUCCUGAGUUGGAGUUGUGUGGGGGCAGUGGGGAUCCUCGCCUUGGUCUCCUUCACAUGUGUGGGCUAUGCGGUCACCAAGGCCCACCCUGCCCUGGUGUGCGCUGUCCUACAUUCCGAGGUGGUUGUGGCCCUUAUACUGCAGUAUUAUAUGCUCCAUGAGACUGUGGCACCUUCUGACAUCGUGGCGGCAGGGGUUGUGCUGGGCAGCAUUGCCAUCAUUACAGCCCAGAACCUCAGCUGUGAGAGGACAGGGAGGGUGGAGGAGUGAGAUAGAACUUGGGAGCCCGGGGGUUGGGAGGGACAGGGAUAAAUAAAGGCAAAGACUGAAGACAAACAUGGGAGGAGAAGUGACUGGAAAAGAACUGGUGUGGGAGAGGGAUACCUCUCAGAGUCAAGGGUGACUUGGGGACUUGGUGGAGAGGGACUACGUGGAAGACCUGGGGCCAGCCUGGGACCAAGGGAUGUGGAGUCCAGGCUGGGUCCUAGAAUCAGGGCAUAACUAAGGGGUAAAGUCUGAGGAGCAGAUCCAAAGGGCUGAGGCAGGGAGGCCGUGGGCCAUGGGGAGGACUUCACUCAGCAGCAAAGAGAAGAGCAUUGGGGCUGGAGUGUUCCGGCAAAGACAGAGCCAGCAGCUGCGCUGGGGGAGGGAAGCGUGCCUCCCCACCCCUCCCCUCACGGGGAAGGUUUCCUUUCCUCGUGCUUGUGCCCCCCGCUUGGGGUGGUGACGUGACAUUGACAUCAAACAAGGAUUACAGUGAAUGUGAAAAAAAAAAAAAAAGAUACCUGAAUAGACAUUUCUAUGACAUUUUAAAAGCCAUGAAUUUAUUUUGGCACAAAUAUUUUAUCAUAUGCAGUCACUUCUUUGUAAAUGAUUUUUUGUAAAGUCAUUGGAUAUAAAAGAGUGAUUUUCCUCACCUGAGUACAUGAAAAGAAAAUGCUGAAAUCAAUGUAUAAAUCAAAUCAUCUGUACUAGCACUGUUAAUCUAGAAGAAAGUGGUUGCAUAGAGAAGAGUAAGAAUGUAGACCAGCUUAUUGAAGU